AUAUACACUCUUUGGAGUCUGAAAUAUGGAGGAUGCAGCUGCACUUGACUGACCGAUUAAAAGAUUUCCCUUGACUUUGAGAAACGAUAUUUAAUCAGAACAAAAUACUGUGCACUAAAGAUGGAGUUUUCCUGGGGAAGCGGCCAGGAAUCCCGGCGUCUGCUGCUCUUACUUCUUCUCCUCGCAGCCUGGGAGGCAGGGAACGGUCAGCUCCACUACUCGGUCUCCGAGGAGGCCAAACACGGCACCUUCGUGGGCCGCAUCGCGCAGGACCUGGGACUGGAGCUGGCGGAGCUGGUGCCGCGCCUGUUCCGGGUGGCGUCCAAGGGCCGCGGAGGCCUUCUGGAGGUAAAUCUGCAGAAUGGCAUUUUGUUUGUGAAUUCUCGGAUCGACCGGGAGGAGCUGUGCCGGCGGAGCGCGGAGUGCAGCAUCCACCUGGAGGUGAUCGUAGACAGGCCGCUGCAGGUUUUCCAUGUGGACGUGGAGGUGAGGGACAUUAACGAUAACCCGCCGGUGUUCCCAGCAACACAAAAGAACCUGUCCAUCGCGGAAUCCAGGCCGCUUGACUCUCGGUUUCCACUAGAGGGCGCCUCGGAUGCAGAUAUCGGGGAGAACGCCCUGCUCACUUACAGACUGAGCCCAAAUGAAUACUUUUCUCUGGAAAAACCACCUGAUGACGAGCUGGUAAAAGGUCUUGGGCUUAUAUUACGGAAAUCUUUAGACAGAGAAGAAGCUCCGGAGAUUUUUUUAGUGCUCACAGCCACUGAUGGAGGCAAACCCGAGUUGACUGGCACCGUUCAGUUACUCAUCACAGUACUGGAUGCCAAUGACAAUGCCCCAGCUUUUGACAGAACCAUUUAUAAGGUGAGAUUACUAGAAAAUGUUCCUAAUGGAACAUUGGUAAUUAAACUUAACGCCUCAGAUUUAGACGAAGGAUUGAAUGGGGACAUUGUUUAUUCAUUCUCAAAUGAUAUUUCGCCAAAUGUGAAAUCCAAGUUUCACAUAGAUCCAAUUACUGGACAAAUUAUUGUAAAGGGAUAUAUUGACUUUGAAGAAAGCAAAUCCUAUGAAAUUAUUGUAGAGGGCAUUGAUAAGGGACAGCUCCCACUUUCUGGCCAUUGUAGAGUUAUUGUGGAAGUAGAAGACAACAACGAUAAUGUCCCAGAUUUGGAAUUCAAGUCUUUAUCACUUCCAAUUAGAGAGGACGCUCCACUGGGUACAGUCAUCGCCCUGAUCAGCGUGUCCGACAAAGACAUGGGUGUCAAUGGGCUGGUCACCUGCUCCUUGACGUCCCACGUCCCCUUCAAGCUGGUGUCCACCUUCAAGAAUUACUACUCGUUGGUGCUGGACAGUGCCCUGGACCGCGAGAGCGUGUCAGCCUAUGAGCUGGUGGUGACCGCGCGAGACGGGGGCUCGCCUUCGCUGUGGGCCACGGCCAGUGUUUCUGUGGAGGUGGCUGAUGUGAACGACAACGCUCCGGCGUUCGCGCAGCCCGAGUACACAGUGUUCGUGAAGGAGAACAACCCGCCGGGCUGCCACAUCUUCACUGUGUCUGCGUGGGACGCGGACGCGCAGGAGAACGCGCUGGUGUCCUACUCGCUGGUAGAGCGGCGGGUAGGGGAGCGCGCGCUGUCGAGCUACGUUUCGGUGCAUGCGGAGAGCGGCAAGGUGUACGCGCUGCAGCCGCUGGACCACGAGGAGCUAGAGCUGCUGCAGUUUCAGGUGACCGCUCGCGAUGCCGGCGUGCCACCUCUGGGCAGCAACGUGACGCUGCAGGUGUUCGUGCUGGACGAAAACGACAACGCGCCAGCACUGCUAGCGCCUCGGGCGGGUGGCACUGGUGGCGCAGUGAGCGAGCUGGUGCCAUGGUCGGUGGGUGUGGGCCACGUGGUGGCAAAGGUGCGCGCGGUGGAUGCUGACUCGGGCUACAACGCGUGGCUUUCGUACGAGCUGCAGCCGGGGACUGGUGGCGCGCGCAUCCCGUUCCGCGUGGGGCUGUACACUGGCGAGAUCAGCACAACGCGUGCCCUGGACGAAACGGACGCUCCGCGCCACCGCCUACUGGUACUGGUGAAGGACCACGGCGAGCCCGCGCUGACGGCCACGGCCACUGUGCUGGUGUCACUUGUGGAGAGUGGACAGGCGCCAAAGGCCUCCUCACGGGCGUUGGUGGGCGCUGUGGGUCCCGAUGCUGCGCUGGUGGAUGUCAACGUAUACCUGAUCAUUGCCAUCUGCGCGGUGUCCAGCCUUUUGGUGCUCACGCUGCUGCUGUACACCGCGCUGCGGUGCUCUGCGCUGCCCACCGAGGGCGCGUGCGCUCCGGGCAAGCCCACGCUGGUGUGCUCCAGUGCGGUGGGGAGCUGGUCAUACUCGCAGCAGAGGAGGCCGAGGGUGUGCUCUGGUGAGGGCCCACCCAAGACCGACCUCAUGGCCUUCAGCCCCAGUUUACCUGACUCUAGGGACAGAGAAGAUCAGCUGCAGACAACUGAGGAAUCCUUUGCAAAGGUUAGUGUAUAACAUCCUUUUGUUUAAUUUUCGUAUUGUUUUUCUCUAUCAACUUCUUCGUAAAUUUAUUUCUAAGAGUCAAAUUUCCCUGGGUUAAAAUUUUACCUCUUUUUACAUAUCCAUUUUAACUAAAGUCUUUUGGAAUUAUAGGACAUCAGAGCAAUAUAUAUUGCCUUCCUUCAUUUUAUGCUGCAUUAUUCAAUGCAUAUUAACAGAACUGUAAUUUCUAGUAAAUUUUCACUAUAUUCACCCUCUUUGUUUUUGGUAAUAAUCAACAUUUUAGAAAACAUUUUACUAUUAUUUAACCUAUUACAUAUAAACAAAUGUGCACAGGCUGAAAUAAUAAAGCUCCAUAAAUUGUAUGAAAGUGAAAAGCUCCGUUGCCUCCAUCGCUGAAGCCCCUCGCAUGCACCUGCCAAAUCACUUCCCUUAUUUUUCCUCCAGUGUAACCGCACAUUUGCCUUUUAUAACUGUUUGUUCGGGGCCUGUUUUGGGAACGUUAUCUAAUUGGACUUGCACAACAUGUAUUGUCUGUGCAUUUGUGUGUUAUUUGUAUUUAUCACUCAUUGUUUAUGAAAUUAUCCAUGUUGUUAUAUGUAGUUGUAGUUUAUUUAUUUCUGUUUCUAGUACUAUUUCAUAAAUAUACUAUACCUUAUUUAUUCUACUGUUCAGGAAUUUGCAUUGUGCCUCAAUGUCUAUUUCAAAUAAUGCCAUCAUAAAUAUAUUGUACAUUUCUUUGAUGCCCAUGUACACAGAUUUCUCUCAGGUUUUUGCCUAAGAGUUGUGUUUGUGGGUCACAGAAUAUGUGUGUAUCUUUGUCUUUUGUAGCUAACACCAACCAAUUUUCCAAGAUGUUUUUACCUGUUUACAUUCCUAGUAGUGCAUAAGGCUUUCUGCUGGGCCACAUCAUCUCUACAUUUGUCAGGUUAUUUUCAUGUUAGCCAUUUUACUGGGUGACUUUUGUAAUCUCAUUUUGAAAUUAUUUUAUAUUUAAAUGAAGUUGAGUACCUUUCUAUUUUAUUUUGGCAAUUUUUAUACCUUAUUUUGUGCAAUAGCUGCUCAAAUCUCCUAUUUCUCUAGUCUGUUGUUUUUCUUUUCUUUUUUCUCUUCUUUUUGCUUCCAUAGAACUUUAUUUAUUUCCUUAUCUUGUUUUUCUUAUUACUUAAACAAAUCUUGUAUUCUGAACAUAACUCCUUUUUUUAGUAGUUUUCAACCUCAUGGCUAGUUUUUAAUUCUUUUUUGUCUUUUGGUGAAUAGAAAGUCAUAAUUUUGAUUAAACUCAAUUUAUCAAUUUUUGCUUCUGAUCCUAUUUCACAAAGAUAAUUUUCUGUGGUAUCUUUUAUUUCAUUGUUUACAUUACAUCUACAAUCCAUUUGGAAUAUACAUAUUUUUAUCAUUGUUGUGAGGUAGGGGUCAAGAUUUAUUUUUAUUUCUUCUUAUUAUUUUUAUUAUACUUUAAGUUCUAGGAUACAUGUGCACAACGUGCAGGUUUGUUACAUAGGUAUACAUGUGUGCCAUGUUCGUUUGCUGCACCCAUCAACUCAUCAUUUACAUUAGGUAUUUCUCCUAAUGCUAUCCCUCCCCCAGUCCCCCACACCUCAACAGGCCCCAGUGUGUGAUGUUCCCCACCCUGUGUCCAAGUGCUCUCGUUGUUCAAUUCCCACCUAUGAGUGAGAACAUGCAGUGUUUGGUUUUCUGUGCUUGUGAUAGUUUGCUCAGAAUGACGGUUUCCAGCUUCAUCCAUGUCUCUACAAAGGACAUGAACUCACCCUUUUUUACGGCUGCAUAGUCUUCCAUGGUGUAUAUGUGUCACAUUUUCUUAAUCCGGUCUAUCAUUGAUGGACAUUUGGGUUGGUUCCAAGUCUUUGCUAUUGUGAAUAGUGUCGCAAUAAACAUACAUGUGCAUGUGUCUUUAUAGUAGCAUGAUUUAUAAUCCUUUAGAUAUAUACCCAGUAAUGGGUCAAAUGGUAUUUCUAGUUCCAGAUCCUUGAGGAAUCGCCACACUGUCUUCCACAAUGGUUGAACUAGUUUACACUCCCACCAACGGUGUAAAAGCGUUACUAUUUCUCCACAUCCUCUCCAGCAUGUGUUGUUUCCUGACUUUUUAAUGAUUGCCAUUCUAACUGGUGUGAGAUGGUAUCUCAUUGUGGUUUUGAUUUGCAUUUCUCUGAUGACCAGUGAUGAUGGGCAUUUUUUCAUGUGUCUGUUGGCUGCAUAAAUGUCUUCUUUUGAGAAGUGUCUGUUCAUAUCCUUUGCCCACUUUUUGAUAGGGUUUUUUGUUUUUUUCUUGUAAAUGUGUUUAGGUUCUUUGUAGAUUCUGGAUAUUAGCCCUUUGUCAGAUGGGUAGAUUGCAAAAAUUUUCUCCCAUUCUGUAGGUUGCCUGUUCACUCUGAUUGUAGUUUCUUUUGAAGAUUUAUUUUUUACUACCAUUUUUUUGUUGGACUUUUAAAAUGAGUUUGGAAGUGUUCCCUCUCCUUCAAUUUUUUUUUUUUGGAAGAGUUUGAAAACAAUUAUCAUUGAUUCUUCUUUAAAAGUUUGGUAGAAUUCUCCAGGAAAGAUAUCUGGUUUUGGGCUUUUGUUGUUGUUGUUGUUAGGAGGUUUGGAUUACUGAUUCAAUCUCCUUACUAGUUACAGCUUUGUUUAGAUUUUUUAUGAUUAUGUCUUGGUAGUUUGUAUGUUUCUAGGAAUUAAUCAAUUUCUUCUAGGUUAUUGAAUUUUUUGGUAUAUGAUUUUAAAAGCCUCUUAUAAUUGUGGCAUCAGGUGUAAUGCCACCUCUUUUGUUUCUGACUUCCAGUCUUUUUGUUUUUUUCUUAGUCUAGCUAAGGGGCUUGUCAGUUUUGUUGUUUUUUCAAAAAAUCAACUAAGUUUAAAAACUUAAUUUAAACUUUUUUUCAUUUAUUUUUGCUCUAAUCUUUAUUAUAGUAUUUCCUCCCUUUGCUUUGGGCUUCCUCAUUUGUCCUUUUUUUCUAGUUCCUUGAGUUGUUAAGUUUUUUAUUUGAGAUCUUUCUUCUUUCUUCAUUUUUAGUGUAGGCAUUUACAACUCCCUUCUUUGUUUUUGUUUUCAUGUUUAAGAGACAAGAUCUCACUAUGAUGUACAGAGGCACGAUCAUAGCUCCCUGCAAGUGAUCCUUGUGCCUUGGAUUCCCAAAGCACUGGGAUUACAGGCGUGAGCCACUGAGCUUGCCCAGCUUAAUAUUCCUUCUUAGUACUGCUUUUGUUGUAUCCUGUAAGUUUUUAUUGUGUUGUGUUUUCAUUUUUGUUUAUCUUAACAUAUUUUCUAAUUCAUCUUUUGAUUUCCCCUUUCAUUCAAAUGAAAUUUUGAACAGAAUUUCGUUCAAAAUUCUGUUGUUUAAUUUCUACAUAUUUGCAGAUUUUCCAGUUUUAAUUCCAGUAUUGAUUUCUAGUUUUAUUCCACUGUGGUCAGAAAAGAUAUUUAGUAGGAUUUCAACCUUCUUGAAUUUGUUAAGACUUGUUUUGUGACCUGACGUGUGAUUUAUCCUGGAAAAUGCUCUGAGUGUGCUUGAGAAGACUGUAUAUUUGCUGCUGUUGGGUGGAAUUUUCUGUAUAUGUCUGUUAGUUCCAUUUCAGCUAUAGUGUUGUUCAAGUCCUCUGCUUCCUUGCUGAUUUUCUGUCUGAAUGUUCUAUUCCUUAUUGAAAGUAGGAUACCAAAAUCUCCUACUACAGUCAUUGGAGAUACAUUCUGAGAAUUGUAUCAUUCUGAGAUUUCAUCACUGUGCAAACAUGAGAGUGUACUUACAUAUUUACACAAACCUAGAUAGUAUAGCCUACUACAGACCUAGGUUACAUGAUCUAUUGCUUCUAGGCUACAAACCUGUACAUAUGUUAACUGUACUGAAUACUAUAGGGAAUUGUAACACAAUGGUAAGUAUUUGUAUACCUAAAUAUAUCUAAACAUCUAAAAGGUACAGUAAAAACAUUGUACAGAUUUUUAAAAUGGUACACCUGAAUAGGGUACUUACCCUAUGAAUGGAGACUGCGGGGCUGGAAAUUUAUCUGCAUGAGUCAAUGAGUGAAUGGUGAGUGAAUGUGAAGGCCCAGGACAUUACUGUGCACUAAUGUAGACUUUAAAGCACUAUACAUUUAGGCUACACUCAAUUUAUCAAAAAAUUUUCUUUUUACAGGCUGGUCAUGGUGGCUCAUGCCUGUAAUCCCAGCACUUUGGGAGGCUGAGGAAGGAGGAUCACUUAAGCCCAGGAGUUCAAGACCAGCCUGGGCAAUAUAGUGAGACCCUGUCUCUAGAAAAUAAUUUUUAAAAAUUAGCUAGGUGUGGUGACACACACUUGUAGUUCCAGCUACUCAGGAGGCUGAAGUGGGAGGAUCCUUGACUUGAGGAGGUCAAGGCUACAGUGAGCUAUGGUCGUGCCACUGCACUCCAGCCUGAGCAACAGAGUGAGACUCUGUCUCAAUUUUUUUUCUUUCUUCAGUAAUAAAUUAACCUUAGCUUACUGUAACUUUUCAACUUUGUAAACUUAAAUUUUUUAACCUUUUGACUCUUUUGUAAUAACGCUUAGCUUAAAACACAAACACAUUGUACAGCUGUACAAAAAUAUUUUCUCUUUAUAUCCUUAUUUUACAAGUUUUUUUGACUUUUAAUUUUUUUAUUUUUUUCACUUUUACUUAGUGUUUUUUUUUGUUGUUGUUGUUAAAAAUGAAGAUAUAAACACCCAUACUAGCCUAGGACUGUAUUGGGUCAGGAUCAUCAAUAUCAUUGUCUUCCACCUCCAUAUCUUGUCCCACUGGAAGGUCUUCUGGGGCAGUUACACAUGCGAUGCUAUCAUCUCCUAUGAUAACAAUAUCUUCUAGUGGAAUACUUCCCAAAAGACUUUCCUGAGGCUGUUUUGUGGUGACCUUUUUUCUUUUUUUUUUUUGAGUUAAUGUAUUUUUUAUAAGUAGAAAGAGUACACUGUAAAAUACCACUAAAAAGUAUAGUAAAUACAUAAAGCAGUAACAUUUACUAUCUGUAUCAAGUAUUAUGUACUGUAAAUUACUGUACAUAAUUGUAUGUGCUAUCUUGUACUUUUAUAUAACUGGUAGUGCAAUAGGUUUGUUUACACCAACAUCACCACAAACAUGUGAGUAAUGUGCUACAACAUUAUGACUGCUACAUCAUCACUAGGUGAUAGGAAUUUUUCAGCUCCAUUAUAAUCUUAUGGGACUACUCUUGUACAUGUGGUCUGUUAUUGGUUGAAACGUUGUUAUACAACACUUGACUUUAUUGUAUUGCUAUCUAUUUCUCCAUUUCUGUGAAUGUUUGCCUCAUAUAUUUAGGUGUUUUAAUGUUGGGUGCAUAUGUAUUUAUAAUUGCUAUGUCCUUCUGGUGAAUUGACCUUUUAUCAUUAUAUAAUGUCCUUCUUUGUCUCUUAUGACACUUUUUGACUUAAAGACUAUUUUGUGUGAUGUAGCUGUUUCCACAUUUGCACUCUUUUGGUUACAAUUUGCAUGAAAUUUUUUUAAUAUCCUUUAACUUUCAGGCUAUCCAGGUCUUUAAAUCUAAAGCAAAUCUCUUGUAGUUAGCAUAUAAUUGGGUCUUUAAAAAAAAUCAAUUCAACCACUUUGUAUCUUUUGAUUGGGGGAGUUUAUCCCAUUUUUAUUUAAAGUAAUUAUUGAUAGGGCAUAACUUACUGUUGCCUCUUUGUUAAUUGUUGUUUGCAGCUUGUAGACUUUUUGCUCCUCUUUCCUCCUCUUACUGUCUUCCUUUGUGUUUUAUUGAGAAUUGUAAUGCUAUGUUUUUGUUCCUUUCCUGUUUUCUUUUGUAUAUCUUCCAUAGGUAUUUUCUUUGUGGUUACCAUGGGGCUUACAUUUUAAAACUCUUAUAAAAAUGUAUUUUAAACUGAUAGCAUCUUUACUACAAUCACAAAACAAAACUCAUUAUGUUUACUUCUCCCCUACCCAAAUUUUAUGUUAUUGAUGUCAUAAAUACAUCUUUUUAUAUUGUGUAUACAUUAUUUUAUAGUUAGUUUUUCUGUACUUUUGUCUUUUAAUCAGAUUUUAAAAUAUCAGAUUUUAAAGUGACUUUUGUACCACCAUUACAGUAUUAUAGUAUUCUGUUUUUAUCUAUAUAUUUAUCUUUACUAGUGAGCUUUAUACUUUAAUAAAAUACCUAUGUAUUUCUGUUUAGCAUCCCCUAAUUUUAACUCAAAAGGCCCCCUCUUAACAUUUCUUGUAAGGCAAGUCUAAUUGUGAUCACCUUCAGCUUUUGUUUAACUGGGAAGGUCUUUAUCUCUUUUUCAUUUUUGAAGACAAACUUUGGUGGAUUUGGUAUUCUUGGCUGGCAGUUCUUUUUCUUUUCAGCACUUUCAGUAUAACAUCUCACCCCUUUCUGGAUGGCAAGGUUUCUACUGAGAAAUCUACUGGUAGAGUUAGGGGUGUUCUUUUGUACGUGAUGAGGCAUUUUUCUUUUGCUGCUUUCUAAAUUCUUAACAUUUCUUGGAUCUUGAUGUCCAUUUCCUUCCUCAUAUUUGGGAAGUUUUCAGAUGUAAUUUUAAAAAAUAAGCUGUCUGUCCUUUUCUCUUAUGGCUUCUUCUUUUGAAACUGUCAUAAUGAGUAGAGCAGCCUGCUCGAGGAUGUCCUAUCAAUUUCUUAGGCUUUCUUUACUCUCUUUCAUUUCUUGCUCUUUUUGCUACUCUGUCUGGAUAAUUUCAAAUGAUGUGUCCUUGAGUUCACUGACUCAUUCUUCUACUUGAUUAAGUCUGCUGUUGAACAUGUCUGUAAAAUUUUCAGUUCAAUUAUUGUAUUCUUCAGUUCCAAAAUUUCUUUUUAGUUCUUUUGAAUAUUUUCUAUCUGCUGAAAUUCUGAUUCUGCUUAUGCAUUAUUUUCCUGAGCUCACUGAACAUCUUUAUGACAAUUAUUUUGAAUACUUUGUCAAGUAAUUCACAUAGCUCUAUUUCUUUAGGUUUGGUUUCUGGAGGUGUGUUUGUGUGUGUGUGUGUGUGUGUGUGUGGGCACGCACUAUUUGAUUGGGCCAUGUUUCCUGUUUUCUCAUAUUCCUUAUUACUUUGUGUUGAUAUCUAUACAUUUCAAAAAAACAAAAAACAACAACACACCAGCUACCUCUUCCAGUCUUUAUGGACUGGAUUUGUACAUGGAAAGAUCUUUACUAAUCAGGCUGGCUAGAGAUUCUAGGGACCUCUCAAACCUUUUCUGUGGAUGCAUCUUCUAUGGACUUGUGUGUAUAAUUCCUAAUUAGAGGGAUCUGCCAGCUUUUUUUUUUAAGAUGCUCUAAUCUUUUUCCCUCUGUGGUGUCUGUGUGCUGUACUGUGGGCCCUCUGGAGCAGCAGUAUUCACUCAGCUCUUUUAGGUUCUGAGAAGCCCUCAGUUAUAGAUUCUGCUGAAUCCUAUCAGUGCCUGGAGUCAAGUGAGACAGAAACUUGGACUGCCCACUAAAAUUCAGGAACUUUGGAUGCAUUUUACUCUCUCUUUCCCUCAUGAGAGAGAGAGUGCUGAGCUGAGUUUCUCUCUGUGUGCUGUAUCACAGGUCCUGAGGAGCAUCAGCCCGCCACCCAGCUCUUUAUUAUUCUGAGCUGCCCUCAGGAUUUUAGAAUAUGCCAGGUUCCAUCAGUGCUCUGAGAUAUGCAAGACAGCUCCCCUGAAAAGUCAGAACACUGAAUGCAUGCUUUACUUUCUCUUUCCCUUCUCAGGGAGAAGACAGGAGCUGGGAAUUUCCCCCUGUUUGAAUGGAACUGUGCUGCUGGAUGGGACUAUAGGGAAAGUGCCCCAGAAAAGUGCCCAGCUAGUUUUACACUUGCUUGGAGCCCAGGACCCUCUUAACUGGUUUCGGCACUUAUCACCAUGGGAAUUGGUCCUUGUAUUGUUGUUGAGUUGGUAUACCUGUGGAGGGUCUGGGGAUUCCUAUAACAGCAUCUUGCUGAUGUCACUACCUCUGUUAUCUUUUUAAGCUAUAUAUGCUUUUACAAAUUAUUUUAUUGAUUUCCUCUUUUGUUGAUUAUAACACACAUCCUUGACUUAUUACCUCAAUUAAAUCAAUAAUUUUAAUAAUUCCA